GUUUCGGUCCCCCCUCCGCGUCCCGGGCGGCGGGGCCUCCGGUCGCCCGCCCUCGGGGCAGCUAGUGGCGCAGCCCCCCGCCCGCGGCCCUGGCCUCCCGGGCGGCGCGGCAGGGGAGGGGUUAAGCUGCCGCAGGGACCGCCGCGUGCGGGGCGAGAGGGAGCCCCCGGUGGGGGUGGCGCAGCCGGCGGGGUUCGGUCCGAGCCCGGUGGGAGGCUCCCGGAGCGCAGCCUGGGCCCAGCCCACCCCGCGCCGGCGGCCAUGGCAGGCACCCUGGACCUGGACAAGGGCUGCACGGUGGAGGAGCUGCUCCGCGGGUGCAUCGAAGCCUUCGGUGAGUGGCUCGGGAGGGCACACGGAGCCUGAGCCUAGCCCCGAGUCUGAGCCCGGGUCCCUGCCUCCCAGGCACAGUCCAGGGCACAGCCCUGACCCGGACCCACCCUGCUCCGCAGCGUGCAGUCUCUUUAACGAAAGCCUCCUCCGCAACGCAGGGCAGAGAGAUGCACGCCCUUCAGACAGAUGAGGUUUCCCUUCUCUAGCCUUCCCCAGCGGCGGCGAAGGGAGGGCCGGGUCCCGGACUCUGACACUUGAGGGGCAUUAUCUGUCUCCCGGGGAAUCCGGAGGAACUCGCUAUCUCCGGCCUGGGAGCUGUUUCCGGCUAAUGGGGGGCGGCUUAUCUGGUGAAGGGGUGCCCCUUCCCCCCAAGCGCUCAGGAAAUGACCUCUGGAUUCUUGACCCCGGGGAACCCAGGCUCCUUCCGCCCCAGCUGGUUCCCCUCCGGACGAUGGGCGGCUCGGGCGCUCCCCUCCUCCAGUCCUCAGGGCGUGCCUAUCUCUCGCCCACCACACCUUUCCUCUCUAAUUUGCCUCCUGCUCUCGGAGUCCUGGGCAAGCAGGAGGUGGGCGGGGUCGAGCGUGCACCCGAAGGACCGAUACCUGGCGGGUUGCGGGGUGAGGAUGAGGCAUGGUAGCUGCGGACCCAGCUCAGCCACCUGUCUUUGACCCUUCGGAGUCAGAUGACUCCGGGAAGGUGCGGGACCCGCAGCUGGUGCGCAUGUUCCUCAUGAUGCACCCCUGGUACAUCCCCUCCUCUCAGCUGGCGGCCAAGCUGCUCCACAUCUACCAACAAUCCCGGAAGGACAACUCCAAUUCCCUGCAGGUGAAAACGUGCCACCUGGUCAGGUACUGGAUCUCCGCCUUCCCAGCGGAGUUUGACUUGAACCCGGAGUUGGCUGAGCAGAUCAAGGAGCUGAAGGCUCUGCUAGACCAAGAAGGGAACCGACGGCACAGCAGCCUAAUCGACAUAGACAGCGUCCCUACCUACAAGUGGAAGCGGCAGGUGACUCAGCGGAACCCUGUGGGACAGAAAAAGCGCAAGAUGUCCCUGUUGUUUGACCACCUGGAGCCCAUGGAGCUGGCGGAGCAUCUCACCUACUUGGAGUAUCGCUCCUUCUGCAAGAUCCUGUUUCAGGACUAUCACAGUUUCGUGACUCAUGGCUGCACUGUGGACAACCCCGUCCUGGAGCGGUUCAUCUCCCUCUUCAACAGCGUCUCACAGUGGGUGCAGCUCAUGAUCCUCAGCAAACCCACAGCCCCGCAGCGGGCCCUGGUCAUCACACACUUUGUCCACGUGGCGGAGAAGCUGCUACAGCUGCAGAACUUCAACACGCUGAUGGCAGUGGUCGGGGGCCUGAGCCACAGCUCCAUCUCCCGCCUCAAGGAGACCCACAGCCACGUUAGCCCUGAGACCAUCAAGCUCUGGGAGGGUCUCACGGAACUAGUGACGGCGACAGGCAACUAUGGCAACUACCGGCGUCGGCUGGCAGCCUGUGUGGGCUUCCGCUUCCCGAUCCUGGGUGUGCACCUCAAGGACCUGGUGGCCCUGCAGCUGGCACUGCCUGACUGGCUGGACCCAGCCCGGACCCGGCUCAACGGGGCCAAGAUGAAGCAGCUCUUUAGCAUCCUGGAGGAGCUGGCCAUGGUGACCAGCCUGCGGCCACCAGUACAGGCCAACCCCGACCUGCUGAGCCUGCUCACGGUGUCUCUGGAUCAGUAUCAGACGGAGGAUGAGCUGUACCAGCUGUCCCUGCAGCGGGAGCCGCGCUCCAAGUCCUCGCCAACCAGCCCCACGAGUUGCACCCCACCACCCCGGCCCCCGGUACUGGAGGAGUGGACCUCGGCUGCCAAACCCAAGCUGGAUCAGGCCCUCGUGGUGGAGCACAUCGAGAAGAUGGUGGAGUCUGUGUUCCGGAACUUUGACGUCGAUGGGGAUGGCCACAUCUCACAGGAAGAAUUCCAGAUCAUCCGUGGGAACUUCCCUUACCUCAGCGCCUUUGGGGACCUCGACCAGAACCAGGAUGGCUGCAUCAGCAGGGAGGAGAUGGUUUCCUAUUUCCUGCGCUCCAGCUCUGUGUUGGGGGGGCGCAUGGGCUUCGUACACAACUUCCAGGAGAGCAACUCCUUGCGCCCCGUCGCCUGCCGCCACUGCAAAGCCCUGAUCCUGGGCAUCUACAAGCAGGGCCUCAAAUGCCGAGCCUGUGGAGUGAACUGCCACAAGCAGUGCAAGGAUCGCCUGUCAGUUGAGUGUCGGCGCAGGGCCCAGAGUGUGAGCCUGGAGGGGUCUGCACCCUCACCCUCACCCAUGCACAGCCACCAUCACCGCGCCUUCAGCUUCUCUCUGCCCCGCCCUGGCAGGCGAGGCUCCAGGCCUCCAGAGAUCCGUGAGGAGGAGGUACAGACGGUGGAGGAUGGGGUGUUUGACAUCCACUUGUAAUAGAUGCUGUGGUUGGAUCAAGGACUCAUUCCUGCCUUGGAGAAAAUACUUCAACCAGAGCAGGGAGCCUGGGGGUGUCGGGGCAGGAGGCUGGGGAUGGGGGUGGGAUAUGAGGGUGGCAUGCAGCUGAGGGCAGGGCCAGGGCUGGUGUCCCUAAGGUUGUACAGACUCUUGUGAAUAUUUGUAUUUUCCAGAUGGAAUAAAAAGGCCCGUGUAAUUAACCUUCA